AGCCGGGCCCUGCCUUCCAGAGCUCCUGGAGCGGCCUGUCCCCCGGGACACCGGGACCCACCUGCAGAGGGCUUACCGCUCAGGAGAGCAGAACAAGGCCAACCUGGAGAGGUAGGCAGUGGCUACCUCCACUUUACAGAUGAAGACACUGAGGCUCAGGAGGUGGCGUGACUGCUCCGGGUCUCACGCUUAGUAAACGGCCGCAGAACCCUGGUCGGUUUGACGCAAGACCCUGGCGGAUCCCAGAGCCAAAGUAAGCGCUCACCUCCGCCGGACAGGCAGAGCUGGCCUGAACCUCCAGGACUUCAGCCCUUCUAGGAGAAUCUGAUCCCAGGUGAGGGAGGUCACUUGGGGUGUGGCCCAGCAGGCAGGCGGGACUCCAGACUGGGAACGGAAGUCAGCCCUGCUGGGGCUGGGAGCUGAAGCAUCUGUUCCUUCCUCGCGGGUGUGAGACAAGGAAGAGUGAUCAUUGCCACACCAGGAGCUGAAGCCAUGGCCUCAAAGCCUGAGAAGAGGGUGGCAUCGUCUGUCUUUAUCACCCUGGCACCCCCGCGCCGCGAUGUGGCCGUGGCGGAGGAAGUGAGGCAGGCAGUUUGUGAGGCCCGGCGUGGCCGCCCCUGGGAGGCUCCUGCCCCCAUGAAGACACCCGAGGCUGGCUUGGCGGGGAGGCCCAGCCCCUGGACAACCCCUGGCAGAGCUGCAGCCACAGUGCCGGCUGCACCUAUGCAGCUCUUCAAUGGAGGAUGCCCACCCCCUCCUCCUGUCCUGGAUGGUGAGGACGUGCUUCCUGACCUGGACCUCCUCCCACCCCCUCCACCGCCCCCUCCAGUGCUUCUGCCUUCUGAAGAGGAGGCUCCUGCUCCAAUGGGGGCCUCACUCAUUGCAGACUUAGAGCAGCUGCACCUGUCCCCGCCCCCGCCCCCACCACAGGCCCCAGCGGAGGGACCUUCAGUCCAGCCCGGUCCCCUCAGGCCCAUGGAGGAAGAGCUGCCACCUCCCCCGGCAGAACCUGUUGAGAAAGGGGCAUCCACAGACAUCUGUGCCUUCUGCCACAAGACCGUGUCCCCCCGAGAGCUGGCUGUGGAGGCCAUGAAGAGGCAGUACCAUGCCCAGUGCUUCACGUGCCGCACCUGCCGCCGCCAGCUGGCUGGGCAGAGCUUCUACCAGAAGGAUGGGCGACCCCUCUGCGAACCCUGCUACCAGGACACACUGGAGAGGUGCGGCAAGUGUGGCGAGGUGGUCCGGGACCACAUCAUCAGGGCCCUGGGCCAGGCCUUCCACCCCUCCUGCUUCACGUGUGUGACCUGCGCCCGGUGCAUUGGGGAUGAGAGCUUUGCCCUGGGCAGCCAGAACGAGGUGUACUGCCUGGACGACUUCUACAGGAAAUUCGCCCCCGUCUGCAGCAUCUGUGAAAAUCCCAUCAUCCCUCGGGAUGGGAAAGAUGCCUUCAAAAUCGAAUGCAUGGGAAGAAACUUCCAUGAAAAUUGCUACAGGUGUGAGGACUGCAGGAUCCUCCUGUCUGUCGAGCCCACGGACCAAGGCUGCUACCCCCUGAACAACCAUCUCUUCUGCAAGCCAUGCCAUGUGAAGCGGAGUGCUGCGGGGUGCUGCUGAGAGUGCCCGCUGGGCAGUGAACAGACCACUAGCCCCGGCUGGGGCCCUUCCCUGACUUGGUUUCCCUUCCUAACCUGCUCUUGCACACUUUCCUUCUGAGCCUCCAUGGAGACCAGCCUGCAAGCCGGCCCAGCCUGUCCAGGAUACAGUGGGGCUGAGCACCCCCAGGCCUUCCACUCCUCUACCCUCUGGGCACCAGAAGGCUCCUGGACCAUGAGCUUCACCCCCAGAAUUCCCUGCUGACCCUGCCCCACUUCCAGGGAAAAGCUGGGGGAGGUUGGACCCCUCUCACUGACUAGCUGUCUGGUAGGGGUGCUAGGACCAGCCUCGCCUGUGGGGUUGAGCUGUUUGAGGACAAACUCCAAGGUCCCUUAAAAAGUGCCUUUUAGAGGCUGGGCAUGGUGGCUCACGCUUGUAAUCCCAGCACUUUGGGAGGCCAAGGUGGGUGGAUCACCUGAGGUCAGGAGUUCAAGACCAGCCUGGCCAACAUGGUGAAACCCUGUCUCUACUAAAAAUACAAAAAUUAGCCAGGCAUGGUAGCAGGUGCCUGUAAUCCCAGCUACUGGGGAAAGCUGAGGCAGGAGAAUUGCUUCAAUCUGGAAGGCAGAGGUUGCAGUGAGAUUGCACCAUUGCAUUCCAGCCUGGGCAACAAGAGGGAAACUCCGUCUCAAAAAAAAAAAAGUGCCUUUUAGGCCGGAUGUGGUGGCUCAUGCCUGUAAUCCCAGCACUUUGGGAGGCCAAGGCAGGCAGAUCACUUGAGGUCAGGAGUUUGAGACCAGCCUGGCCAACACGGCAAAACCCCGUUUCUACUAAAAAUACAAAAAUUAGCUGGGUGUGGUGGCGUGCGCCUGUAAUCCCAGCUACUCAGGAGGCUGAGGCAGGAGCAUUGCUUGAACCCGGGAGGCAGAGGUUGCAGUGAGCUGAGAUGGCACCACUGCACUCCAGCCUGGGAGACACAGCGAGACUCUGUCUCCAAAAAAAAAAGUGCUUUUUGAAAAUGUUGAGGUUGAAAUGAUGGGAACCAACAUUCUUUGGAUUUAGUGGGGAGCAUAAUAGCAAACACCCCCUUGGUUCGCACAUGUACAGGAAUGGGACCCAGUUGGGGCACAGCCAUGGACUUCCCCGCCCUGGAAUGUGUGGUGCAAAGUGGGGCCAGGGCCCAGACCCAAGAGGAGAGGGUGGUCCGCAGACACCCCGGGAUGUCAGCAUCCCCCGACCUGCCUUCUGGCGGCACCUCCCGGGUGCUGUGUUGAGUCAGCAGGCAUGGGGUGAGAGCCUGGUAUAUGCUGGGAACAGGGUGCAGGGGCCAAGCGUUCCUCCUUCAGCCUUGACUUGGGCCAUGCACCCCCUCUCCCCCAAACACAAACAAGCACUUCUCCAGUAUGGUGCCAGGACAGGUGUCCCUUCAGUCCUCUGGUUAUGACCUCAAGUCCUACUUGGGCCCUGCAGCCCAGCCUGUGUUGUAACCUCUGCGUCCUCAAGACCACACCUGGAAGAUUCUUCUUCCCUUUGAAGGAGAAUCAUCAUUGUUGCUUUAUCACUUCUAAGACAUUUUGUACGGCACGGACAAGUUAAACAGAAUGUGCUUCCCUCCCUGGGGUCUCACACGCUCCCACGAGAAUGCCACAGGGGCCGUGCACUGGGCAGGCUUCUCUGUAGAACCCCAGGGGCUUCGGCCCAGACCACAGCGUCUUGCCCUGAGCCUAGAGCAGGGAGUCCCGAACUUCUGCAUUCACAGACCACCUCCACAAUUGUUAUAACCAAAGGCCUCCUGUUCUGUUAUUUCACUUAAAUCAACAUGCUAUUUUGUUUUCACUCACUUCUGACUUUAGCCUCGUGCUGAGCCGUGUAUCCAUGCAGUCAUGUUCACGUGCUAGUUACGUUUUUCUUCUUACACAUGAAAAUAAAUGCAUAAGUGUUAGAAGCUC